AACUGUCAAUCCGGGGAAGCAGAAGGCCGCACUCAGAGUCUCUGCACUCCUUUGUUGCUGGGGUCCGUUGCGUUCUGCAUCCAGUCCUUGCUGCUCCGAGAGGCCCCAGGUGCCUCCGCCACGGCUCCUGUGACGCUGUCACCUGCGCUGUGACCUGCUCCGGAGUCAUAAAGAGGACGCCGGGACACCAAGAAGCAGGGAAAUGGACCCAAUCCAGUAUACCCCACUGUAUUUAGUUCUCAUGUCUCCUUGAUCUGCUUUGUGACAAUUUCUCAGUCUUCCCUUGUUUUUUAAAAUCACUUUGACAGUUUUAAGAGUGCUGGUCAGGUAUUCCAUAGAAUGUUCCUCAAUUUGGAAUUUUUCUCAUGAUUAGACUGGAGUUAGGUGUUUUGCAGGAGAAUGCCACAAAGGUGAAGUGUCCAGGCUCAUCACUUGAUACACCUGGUGACAGUAACCUUGAUCACUUGAUUGAAGCAGUGUUUGUCAGGUUUCUCCACUUUAAAGUUACUAUUUUUACCCCUUUCCAUACUCUGUUCUUUGGAAGUGAGUCACUAAGUCCAGCACAGGUCCAAGGGAGGAGGGCCAAUUCAGCUCCAUAGUUCUGGAGGCUGGGAAGUCUAAGAUCAAGGCACGCCAGGCACGGUGGCUUACGCCUGUAAUCCCAACACUUUGGGAGGCCAAGGUGGGCAGAUGACGAGAUCAGGAGUUUGAGACCAGCCUGACCAACAUGGUGAAACCCCGUCUCUACUAAAAAUACAAAAAUUAGCUGGGCAUGGUGGUGCGUGCCUGUAAUCCCAGCUACUCAGGAGGCUGAGGCAGGAGAACUGCUUGAACCCGGGAGGCAGAGGUUGCAGUGAGCCAAGAUCGCGCCACUGCACUCCAGCCUGGGUGACAGAGUGAGGCCCCAUCUCAGACAAAAAAAAAAAAAAAAAAAAAAAAGAUCAAGGCACUGGCAGGUACCAUGUCCAGAGGGUCCAUUCCUCAUGAACUCCAUCCUCUUGCUGUGUCCUCACGUGGCAGAAGGCUACAUUUUCCUAUUCUGCUGUUGCUUUACCCAUAGUUACACUCUGGCAUCAAAGUUGCUGUUUGAGAGGAAGUGAGUGUAGACAGGGGAGUAAGAGGUCUGAUGACAGAGGCAGGGAAUAAAUGUUUGGAGUCCACAGCAUCAUGAGAACUUCUUGGGAAUAGAGUCUAGGCCCCCAGUGCUGUCACUCUCACCCAUCCUCCUCUACACAUGUGAGAUGUUUCAGGACCCAGUGGCCUUUGAGGAUGUGGCUGUGAACUUCACCCAGGAGGAGUGGGCCUUGUUGAAUCCUUUCCAGAAGAUCUCUACAGAGAUGUGAUGCAGGAAACCUUCACGAACCUCAUCUGUAUAGAAAUUUUAUGGGAGAGAGACUCUUUGAGAGUGCAGAAGGUAGUCAGUGUGGAGAAACUUUCACCCAGGUUCCGGAAGACAUGCUGAACAAGAAAACUCUUCCUGGAGUAAAAUCAUGUGAAAGUGGUACAUGUGGAGAAAUCUUCAUGGGAUAUUCAUCCUUUAAUAGGAACAUCAGAACUGACACUGGACACCAACCACAUAAGUGUCAGAAAUUUUUAGAGAAGCCAUAUAAACAUAAACAACGUAGGAAAGCCUUGAGCCAUAGCCACUGCUUUCGAACACAUGAAAGGCCUCACACUAGAGAGAAACCUUUUGAUUGUAAGGAAUGUGAAAAAUCUUUCAUUUCUCCUGCAAGCAUUCGAAGAUAUAUGGUAACGCACAGUGGAGAUGGACCUUAUAAAUGUAAGUUUUGUGGGAAAGCCUUGGAUUGUCUCAGUUUAUACCUUACCCAUGAACGAACUCACACUGGAGAGAAACGAUAUGAAUGUAAACAAUGUGGUAAAGCCUUCAGUUGGCACAGUUCUGUUCGAAUCCAUGAAAGAACUCACACUGGGGAGAAGCCAUAUGAAUGUAAGGAGUGUGGGAAAUCAUUCAAUUUUUCCAGUUCCUUUCGCAGACAUGAAAGGACACACACAGGAGAGAAGCCGUACAAAUGUAAGGAAUGUGGGAAAGCCUUCAAUUGUCCCAGUUCUUUUCACAGGCAUGAAAGGACUCACACAGGAGAAAAACCCUAUGAAUGUAAACUAUAUGGGAAAGCAUUAUCUCGCCUUAUAAGCUUUCGAAGACACAUGAGAAUGCACACUGGAGAGAGGCCUCAUAAAUGUAAGAUAUGUGGGAAAGCCUUUUACUCUCCCAGUUCAUUUCAAAGGCAUGAAAGAAGUCACACUGGAGAGAAACCCUACAAAUGCAAGCAAUGUGGGAAAGCCUUCACUUGUUCCACUUCGUUUCAAUAUCAUGAAAGGACUCACACUGGAGAGAAACCCGAUGGGUGUAAGCAAUGUGGGAAAGCCUUCAGAUCUGCCAAGUACAUUCGAAUACAUGGAAGGACUCACACUGGUGAGAAACCCUAUGAAUGUAAGCAAUGUGGGAAAGCAUUUCAUUGUGUCAGCUCCUUUCAUAGACAUGAAAGGACUCACGCUGGAGAAAAACCUUAUGAAUGUAAGCAUUGUGGGAAAGCCUUCACUUGUUCCAUAUAUAUUAGAAUACAUGAAAGAAUUCACACUGGAGAGAAACCUUACCAAUGUAAGGAAUGUGGGAAAGCCUUCAUUCGUUCCAGUUACUGUCGAAAACAUGAAAGAACUCACACUAUUAAUAUAUGAGAGAAAUGCUAUUUUUUAAUUUUUAUUUUAAUAGAGACAGGGUCUCACUAUCUUGUCCAGGUUGGUCUUGAACUCCUGGCCUCAAGCAUCCCUCCCAGCUUGAAGUGUCAAUAAAGGAAGGCAAUAAAAUGUAGAGAUGGAGUUAGGUGAUGCCACGCUGGGAUUCACUGGUGGCCUAUCUUACAUAUGAUUUCGAAGGCAGACAUGAGGAAGGCCUUAGUCACAUUUUAGAGCCAGCCAAAUUCACAUGGGCUGUGUGGCCCCCUGAUUCUAGCCCAUUUUCCUGAUUCUCUGGCUUGUCAAUCAAGAGUAUCCUCCAAAUCUCUUGACUUUCCUUUUUUCAGAGGUGUAGGUUUCCAAAGAUGUCCCCAGAAGCUCCACAUUCAAGUUCUAUCUACAGUUUGGUUUUUCUUUAAGUAUUGUAAUGUACAUACCAGAGAGAUAAUGCAGACUGUCAUGGGUGGGGAAUGUUCUCUGAUGCUCAACUCCCCUAGUCUGCAGAUUGAGUUGGUAGGAGGUGUGAUUUGUUUACAUGCACCUUUGUUCCUGCUGGUAGUGACCUUGUUCUUGAUUCAGCCUGACAGCUACUAUGCUGCCAUCAGAACCAACUUGAUGAGAGCUCUGCUGCCCUGUGCAGUGACUGGUCUCAUCCAGGACUCUCAUGUGAGAAGGAACACCUUGCUCUGGUCAGGAAAUGUCCAGUGUUUCCUGUUAUCCACAGGAGAAUGUAAUGCCUCAGUUCAUUUUCAGUUAUCUUUGAUUAUAUGUGAUUGACAAUGUGUAUUUUUGAGGGAGCAAAGAUUUCUGUACAUAUUUCUUAAAAAUAGUUUAUUCAGCUGGGUGCAGUGGCUCAUGCCUGUAACCCCAGCACUUUGGGAGGCCGAGGUGGGCGGAUCACGAGGUCAGGAGUUUGAGACUAGCCUGGCCAACACAGUGAAACCCCAUCUCUACUAAAAGUACCAAAGUUAGCCGGGUGUGGUGGUGGAUACCUGUAAUCCCAGCUACUCGGGAGGCUGAGGCAGGAGAAUCUCCUGAACCUGGGAGGUGGAGGUUGCAGUGAGCCAAGAUCACGCCACUGUACUCCAGCCUGGACAAGAGAGCAAUACUCUGUCUCAAAAAAAAAAAAAAAGGUUUAUUCACUGUUUUUCAGUUGUGUACUUGCAAAUGUUUUUCUCUUUUUUUUGUAUACUGAGAAGCUCUAUUAAAAUAUCCCUUGUCAACAUGGAUCAGAUCAAA